ACCCGACAGCUGAGCUCUUUUCAAGAUGGCAGCUGCCUCCCAAGCCUCCUUUUCCUCUGCUUCCUGACAUCCUCCUUGAACUCCAGCCACAGUGACCUAUUCUCUCCCAAAGAAACACCAGGAUUACUCCUUGAAGAGUCCUUAUUCAGGCCCUUUUUGACCCCUGGAAUCCUCUCUCCUUCCAUUCUCUCAACCCAAAUGCCACAAUCUUCCUUACCGUCUGAACCAGGUGUGAGCUCCUAGGGUCAGGGACAGUGACAUUAACAUCUCUGUGUCCCACCUGCUCACAGAACAGGGCCAGUCCUGGAGUGGGCUCUCUGGGACAGUACUCAUCAUCAGGUCCUUCUUGUCUGGGUUUUGUCUGAUUGAAGCCCCUCCUGGGACAGGGGCAGAGCCUUCAACUCUGCUCAAUCCAACCUAUGCUCAUGGAGAUCAGCCCUGAGCCCUGCCCUGUGCGAGGAACAGUGUAAUGGAAGAUGAAUAAGUCCUUCAAGUAUGCCAGCCCAUACCUGGCUCACACUCCUAACACUUGCUGUUUUCUCUGUGGAUCUGCAUGUGGCUGCCUCCUCAUCAUCUAAGGGCUCAGUUCACAUUGUGGGUCUCAUUGUACUUUGGAAUCCUGGGGCUGUGUUCUGUGAUAACUGGAGGGUGCAUUAUCUUUCUGCACUGGAGGAAGAACUUGAGGCGGGAAGAGCAUGCCCAGCAGUGGGUGGAGGUGAUGAGAGCUGCCACAUUCACCUACAGCCCAUUGUUGUACUGGAUUAACAAGCGACGGCGCUACGGCAUGAAUGCAGCCAUCAACACGGGCCCUGCCCCUGCUGUCACCAAGACUGAGACUGAGGUCCAGAAUCCAGAUGUUCUGUGGGAUUUGGACAUCCCCGAAGGCAGGAGCCAUGCUGACCAAGACAGCAACCCCAAGGCGGAAGCCCCUGCUCCCCUGCAACCUGCACUGCAGCUGGCUCCACAGCAGCCCCAGGCCAGAUCCCCAUUCCCACUUCCCAUCUUUCAGGAGGUGCCCUUUGCCCCACCCUUGUGCAACCUACCCCCCCUGCUGAACCACUCUGUCUCCUAUCCUUUGGCCACCUGUCCUGAAAGGAAUGUUCUCUUCCAUUCCCUCCUGAAUCUGGCCCAGGAAGACCAUAGCUUCAAUGCCAAGCCUUUUCCUUCAGAACUGUAGCCUCCUCUCACUGAAGGUGGGAGCUGCAGGAAUCAGGUGCAGAGUAGGAAAUGGAACUAACCUCAGGAAGGUGGUAUUGACAGAGGUCAGGACCCACCUGGAUGUCAUGCUAUGAAACAUUAAAAGAAAAAAAAAAAA